GUCAGUCAGUCCACUGGCUCCCGCGCCGCGUCUGUGUCCGUCGCUCGGAGGGUGGAAGCCGGGGUCUCGCGGGCCGCGGGCCGCAUGACUCCUCUCUGCCUCAAUUGCUCUGUCCUCCCUGGAGACCUGUACCCAGGGGGUGCAAGGAACCCCAUGGCUUGCAAUGGCAGUGCGGCCAGGGGGCACUUUGACCCUGAGGACUUGAACCUGACUGACGAGGCACUGAGACUCAAGUACCUGGGGCCCCAGCAGACAGAGCUGUUCAUGCCCAUCUGUGCCACAUACCUGCUGAUCUUCGUGGUGGGCGCUGUGGGCAAUGGGCUGACCUGUCUGGUCAUCCUGCGCCACAAGGCCAUGCGCACGCCUACCAACUACUACCUCUUCAGCCUGGCCGUGUCGGACCUGCUGGUGCUGCUGGUGGGCCUGCCCCUGGAGCUCUAUGAGAUGUGGCACAACUACCCCUUCCUGCUGGGCGUUGGUGGCUGCUAUUUCCGCACGCUACUGUUUGAGAUGGUCUGCCUGGCCUCAGUGCUCAACGUCACUGCCCUGAGCGUGGAACGCUAUGUGGCCGUGGUGCACCCACUCCAGGCCAGGUCCAUGGUGACGCGGGCCCAUGUGCGCCGAGUGCUUGGGGCCGUCUGGGGUCUUGCCAUGCUCUGCUCCCUGCCCAACACCAGCCUGCACGGCAUCCGGCAGCUGCACGUGCCCUGCCGGGGCCCAGUGCCAGACUCAGCUGUUUGCAUGCUGGUCCGCCCACGGGCCCUCUACAACAUGGUAGUGCAGACCACCGCGCUGCUCUUCUUCUGCCUGCCCAUGGCCAUCAUGAGCGUGCUCUACCUGCUCAUUGGGCUGCGACUGCGGCGGGAGAGGCUGCUGCUCAUGCAGGAGGCCAAGGGCAGGGGCUCUGCAGCAGCCAGGUCCAGAUACACCUGCAGGCUCCAGCAGCACGAUCGGGGCCGGAGACAAGUGACCAAGAUGCUGUCAGCCUGUGAGGCAUGGCCACCGGCACGCCAUCUUCUUUCCUGAGGAACUGCUGUCUUUCCUUAGAGAUGAGUGAAAAAUCCCAAGAAGGAUUCUGAUGGGCGUGGCCUAGGUCAUGCCCCACCUCCUGAGCCAGAGUGGCAGGAUGCCGAGGUGCACAGCCCCCAGUGGAACUACACAGUGAGAUCUGGGGGGAGCAAAGUCCCCCAGAGAAGGGGAGGAGGGUGUUGGAGAGGCCAGGUGCUGAAUUUCCCCCAUGCCAUGUCUGCGGUUCCCUGGGAACCGCAGGAGAGACCAUUUGUCUAAACAGCCCCAUCCCGAGGCGUGUCUGUGAAGGCCGGGCUCAAGGCACAGGGGAUCAGGCCAGAGGCCUGCGGAUUAGGGCAGGCUAAGGUACUGGGAUGAGGCUCUGGAUCUCUGUGGCCUGGACCUGGCUCUUUUUCAAAAGCUGUGGCCCUGGGGAAGCAAGACAAACUGAUACUAAGCCGAUCAAAGAUCCGCCCCAUCCACCUACCUGCAUCCCAGCUCAGCCCCACCUCAGCAGAGCCUGAAUCAGGCCAGUGGGGUGAGCCAGGUCAGCAGAGGGCCACUGAGACUUUGGACAGAGCCAGCUAACUGGGGGCCGCCCCAUCUCCAGAGUGACUCGCUCCUCUCACCCCUCAGACACCGUCCCAGAGCUCAGUCUCUUGUGCAGCUCCUGAAACGAGGCUGACCCCAGAGCUAUGUGCAUGCCUCCCAGCUCUGCACGGUGAAGCCUGUGCUCAGGACCAGCUGCCCACUGCCGCCCUGCCUCCUGCCUACUACCCCGUCCCCUCCCUGAAAACAUGGGUGGGCAGAGUCUGCAGUAGGUGCUUAGCUGGGGUGGCUCACCCCUGGAAGGUGGGCUUCCUGCUUGCUGGCCUUCUCUCUUCCCUCCCUCCCUCCCUUGUCCACUUUCCGCUGGCCCUCUGUGCACCAGGCCAGGGGCCAGGGAGGUUGUGAGCAACGUCCUUUUUGAAAUCUGGGAUUAUGAGGAAAACCAUGCUAGGGUAUGAUGGGGAAGACACUGCCCAGGAAAGCUAGUGAGUUGCAGCAGCAAACCCAAGAAACAAGGAACAAAAAUCACAGCUGACCCUGUGGCAGAGACCCAGGGAAGGGCAUAGUUGGGUAAGAACAAGGCAGGAGGGAUUUGGGGAGAAAGUGAAGGUUUGCCAAACUCUCCUACCUUUUGUUAGGGAGGGGGUGGGCAAGGGCCUGGCAAGUAAGAUGGGGGGCAGGUUAGUGCAGGGCAAGACAUUCAGAUGGGCCUUGGGGAGCUGGGGGCUGGAGCUGAAAAGGCCGGGGCCAAGGCAGGCAGUGUGUGUGUGUGUGCAUGUGUGUGUCUGUGUGUGUGCAUGCAUGUGUGUGUGUGUGCAUGCGUGUGUGUGUCUCACUCUCCCUGGCCCCAUGACCUCCGGUCUGCCGCUCUCUGAGCACGUGCCCCAUUCUUCUUUUCUGUACUUAUGCAUCAGCAAGCAUGGCCCCCAAGUGGGCAUCCAGAGUGGCCCUAGCCCCACAGCUUGUAUCACCCCAGAAGCUCAACAGCCACAGCUAAGUGUCACCCAAUUUCAUAUUCCAGGGUGAGAGAAUCUGAUUGGGCCGGCUGGGCUUAGGUGUCCACACCUGGUCCAGUUGGCUGUGGUCAGAGGCAGGGAUAUGCCCCAUUGCCCACAGUCAGUGACCAUGGUGAGGGCAGCCUCUCUGAGAGAGGCAUGGCCAGAACAGGCAAAUUUCCAGAAACUUCCACCUGGGUGAUAGGUGAGGGUGGCCUGUGGGAUAGGAGAGGAUGUGAAAAUGGGUGACCCAAACUGAAGCCCGGGAAGGCAGCUGAGGGGCCUCGGGCGGGCACUCGGCCUCCCUUCUCUGUCCCUGCAGUUGUCCUGGUCGUGGUGUUUGGCAUCUGCUGGGCCCCGUUCCACGCCGACCGCGUCAUGUGGAGCGUCGUGUCACAGUGGACAGAUGGCCUGCACCUGGCCUUCCAGCACGUGCACGUCAUCUCCGGCAUCUUCUUCUACCUGGGCUCGGCGGCCAACCCCGUGCUCUAUAGCCUCAUGUCCAGCCGCUUCCGAGAGACCUUCCAGGAGGCCCUGUGCCUCGGGGCCUGCUGCCAUCGCCUCAGACCCCGCCACAGCUCCCACAGCCUCAGCAGGAUGACCACAGGCAGCACCCUGUGUGAUGUGGGCUCCCUGGGCAGCUGGGUCCACCCCCUGGCUGGGAACGAUGGCCCAGAGGCGCAGCAAGAGACCGAUCCAUCCUGAGUGGAGCCUUAAAGUGGCUUCACCUGGAGGGGCCAGAGGGUCACCUGGAGCUGGGGAGACACAUCUGCCUUCCUCUGCAGGGAUGCCUUCACGUACUGUCCCUAGUUCAGCCUAGAAAUUCUGACCAGCACCUCAGUUUCCCUCAGAGGGAAACAGCAGGAGGAGGGAUCCCUGACUGCUGAGGACUCACACUGACCAGACGCCACACCUUGUGCUUCUUAUCUGUCCACUGCCACUCCCCCAGUUCAAAUCCUUACCCUGCAGAAAUAUCACAGUUAGCUGGGGCUCAGCAGUCCUCCCUCUGGGGACUCCCUGCCACCACUGCCAGUUUCUGAAACGGUCCCACUGGGUCCUCACUGUCCUUCCCAGUUCCUGUUCAGGUUCUGGCAGGGGCCCAGGGAUCCAGGGGACCUGGUUCCAAUCUCAGCCCUGCUGUCACCACCUUGUCAUGCACCAUCAAGCAUAUCAGUCUACCUUUCUUUUUUUCUGAGACAGAGUCUCACUCUGUCGCCCAGGCUAGAGUGCAGUGGCGCGAUUUUGGCUCACUGCAACCUCCGCCUCCGGGGUUCAAGCGAUUCUCCUGCCUCAGCCUCCCGAGUAGCUGGGACUACAGGUGAGCCCCAGCAUGCCCAGCUAAUUUUUUUUAAUUUUUAGUAGAGACGGGGUUUCACCAUGUUGGCCAGGCUGGUCUCAAACUCUUGACCUCAGGUGAUCCGCCGACCUCGGCCUCCCAAAGUCCUCGGAUUACAGGCAUGAGCCACCACACCCGGCCAAUCAGUCCACCUUUCUAGGCCUUGGUUCCUUGCCUGAAAAAUGAAAGAGGCGCUGGCUUUCCACAGUGUCAUGCUUUGGCACUUUAGCUAUGGUUUUCUUUCUGUGUGUGUGUAAGCCACUGCUUAUAAUAAAACCAACAAUACCCUCAGACUGAAAGGGCGGAAGUUAUUAUCUGCAUCUUUAUCAACCCCAAGCCCCACUUCCUCCCUGACCUCCCCAUGCCCUCCCCAGCCUCUCCCAGCACAAGUGGGGCAAAGCCAGCAUGCAAGCAGACCCCACCACCACAGCCCACCUCCGUCCUCACAUACGUGCAGGCUGGCUCGGGAGUCCAGUGAGCAGAGCAUUGGACUUGGCUGGCCAGAGGGUCUCUGAGGGCAAGAGACAUGGCCAACCAAGGGCAAGGAGUGACCCUGUGGAGGGUUCUGCCGAACUCAAUGCAGUGAGAAGAGGGACAGGGACAAGUAGUCCUUGAAACUGAGCCCCAUUCUGAAUCCCUGCAGGCCAAGUCAUUGCUCAGCCAGGACUCAGUUCAUGGAGGAAACUUGUCCUGCUGCAGUCCCUGAGUCUUGUCCUCCUGAGAGGAAGCCCUGGCUUCCAAGGCUGGGAGCUGGAGGAUGACCUUCGGUCGGUCUGUCUGGGUUCUCCCUGCAGACAGCUUCCUAGCUCAUGCCCAUAGCUCAUGCUCCCUGCCGAGAAAGUGGAGGACGUGGUACAGGGUUGCAGAUGUUUAGUUUUAAAAAUUCAAUUAUAAAAAUAAUAAAUGCUCAUGAUAGAAAAUUUGGAAAGUGCAAAUAAGCAAAAAUGAAAACAAUUUUAAAAAUGUAAAACCUCUCUUGCCAGGGAAUGGGGGAAGGGCAAGUGAGGAGUUCUUUAAUGGGUGAAGAGUUUCAGUUUUGCAAAAUGAAAAAGUUCUGGAGAUCAGUUGUGCAACAAUAUGAAUAUACAUAACAAUACUGAACUAUACACUGAAAUGGUUAAGAUGGUACAUUUUAUGUUAUGUGUAUUUUACCACAAUUUUUAUAAAAAGAGGAUUAAAUCUAAAGGAAAGAAAAAAUUAAAACCACCCAUAACUUUACUCUGAA